GAGACAUUCCUCAAUUGCUUAGACAUAUUCUGAGCCUACAGCAGAGGAACCUCCAGUCUCAGCACCAUGAAUCAAACUGCCAUUCUGAUUUGCUGCCUUAUCUUUCUGACUCUAAGUGGCAUUCAAGGAGUACCUCUCUCUAGAACUGUACGCUGUACCUGCAUCAGCAUUAGUAAUCAACCUGUUAAUCCAAGGUCUUUAGAAAAACUUGAAAUUAUUCCUGCAAGCCAAUUUUGUCCACGUGUUGAGAUCAUUGCUACAAUGAAAAAGAAGGGUGAGAAGAGAUGUCUGAAUCCAGAAUCGAAGGCCAUCAAGAAUUUACUGAAAGCAGUUAGCAAGGAAAGGUCUAAAAGAUCUCCUUAAAACCAGAGGGGAGCAAAAUCGAUGCAGUGCUUCCAAGGAUGGACCACACAGAGGCUGCCUCUCCCAUCACUUCCCUACAUGGAGUAUAUGUCAAGCCAUAAUUGUUCUUAGUUUGCAGUUACACUAAAAGGUGACCAAUGAUGGUCACCAAAUCAGCUGCUACUACUCCUGUAGGAAGGUUAAUGUUCAUCAUCCUAAGCUAUUCAGUAAUAACUCUACCCUGGCACUAUAAUGUAAGCUCUACUGAGGUGCUAUGUUCUUAGUGGAUGUUCUGACCCUGCUUCAAAUAUUUCCCUCACCUUUCCCAUCUUCCAAGGGUACUAAGGAAUCUUUCUGCUUUGGGGUUUAUCAGAAUUCUCAGAAUCUCAAAUAACUAAAAGGUAUGCAAUCAAAUCUGCUUUUUAAAGAAUGCUCUUUACUUCAUGGACUUCCACUGCCAUCCUCCCAAGGGGCCCAAAUUCUUUCAGUGGCUACCUACAUACAAUUCCAAACACAUACAGGAAGGUAGAAAUAUCUGAAAAUGUAUGUGUAAGUAUUCUUAUUUAAUGAAAGACUGUACAAAGUAGAAGUCUUAGAUGUAUAUAUUUCCUAUAUUGUUUUCAGUGUACAUGGAAUAACAUGUAAUUAAGUACUAUGUAUCAAUGAGUAACAGGAAAAUUUUAAAAAUACAGAUAGAUAUAUGCUCUGCAUGUUACAUAAGAUAAAUGUGCUGAAUGGUUUUCAAAAUAAAAAUGAGGUACUCUCCUGGAAAUAUUAAGAAAGACUAUCUAAAUGUUGAAAGAUCAAAAGGUUAAUAAAGUAAUUAUAACUAA